AACUUACACCACAGUUAAAGGAACACCAACCCUCCCAGAUGAGAAUCAGUGCAAGAACUCUGGCAAUUCAAAAAGACACAGUGUCCCCUUGGAAGACCCAGGCCUGCGGAGGGACGUGAGGAGCAGCCCCGACGCCCGACUCAGUCGCAAACACCGGAGUUGGGGAAAACCAAGAGCCUUUGGCCUAGGAGCUGGGAGACUCAGGGCCCUUCUCACACUCAGAAUUGGAGCAGGGCCUUCUAGACAGUCCCAGCACCAUGAGCCCUGAAAAGUCCCAAGAGGAGAGCCCAGAAGAAGACACAGAGAGAACAGAGCGGAAGCCCAUGGUCAAAGAUGCCUUCAAAGACAUUUCCAUAUACUUCACCAAGGAAGAAUGGGCAGAGAUGGGAGACUGGGAGAAAACUCGCUAUAGGAAUGUGAAAAGGAACUAUAAUGCACUGAUUACUAUAGGUCUCAGAGCCACUCGACCAGCUUUCAUGUGUCACCGAAGGCAGGCCAUCAAACUCCAGGUGGAUGACACAGAAGAUUCUGAUGAAGAAUGGACCCCUAGGCAGCAAGUCAAACCUCCUUGGAUGGCCUUAAGAGUGGAACAGCGUAAACACCAGAAGGGAAUGCCCAAGGCGUCAUUCAGUAAUGAAUCUAGUUUGAAAGAAUUGUCAAGAACAGCAAAUUUACUGAAUGCAAGUGGCUCAGAGCAGGCUCAGAAACCAGUGUCCCCUUCUGGAGAAGCAAGUACCUCUGGACAGCACUCAAGACUAAAACUGGAACUCAGGAAGAAGGAGACUGAAAGAAAGAUGUAUAGCCUGCGAGAAAGAAAGGGUCAUGCAUACAAAGAGGUCAGCGAGCCGCAGGAUGAUGAUUACCUCUAUUGUGAGAUGUGUCAGAACUUCUUCAUUGACAGCUGUGCUGCCCAUGGGCCCCCUACAUUUGUAAAGGACAGUGCAGUGGACAAGGGGCACCCCAACCGUUCAGCCCUCAGUCUGCCCCCAGGGCUGAGAAUUGGGCCAUCAGGCAUCCCUCAGGCUGGGCUUGGAGUAUGGAAUGAGGCAUCUGAUCUGCCGCUGGGUCUGCACUUUGGCCCUUAUGAGGGCCGAAUUACAGAAGACGAAGAGGCAGCCAACAAUGGAUACUCCUGGCUGAUCACCAAGGGGAGAAACUGCUAUGAGUAUGUGGAUGGAAAAGAUAAAUCCUGGGCCAACUGGAUGAGGUAUGUGAACUGUGCCCGGGAUGAUGAAGAGCAGAACCUGGUGGCCUUCCAGUACCACAGGCAGAUCUUCUAUAGAACCUGCCGAGUCAUUAGGCCAGGCUGUGAACUGCUGGUCUGGUAUGGGGAUGAAUACGGCCAGGAACUGGGCAUCAAGUGGGGCAGCAAGUGGAAGAAAGAGCUCAUGGCAGGGAGAGAACCAAAGCCAGAGAUCCAUCCAUGUCCCUCAUGCUGUCUGGCCUUUUCAAGUCAGAAAUUUCUCAGUCAACAUGUAGAACGCAAUCACUCCUCUCAGAACUUCCCAGGACCAUCUGCAAGAAAACUCCUCCAACCAGAGAAUCCCUGCCCAGGGGAUCAGAAUCAGGAGCAGCAAUAUCCAGAUCCACACAGCCGUAAUGACAAAACCAAAGGUCAAGAGAUCAAAGAAAGGUCCAAACUCUUGAAUAAAAGGACAUGGCAGAGGGAGAUUUCAAGGGCCUUUUCUAGCCCACCCAAAGGACAAAUGGGGAGCUGUAGAGUGGGAAAAAGAAUAAUGGAAGAAGAGUCCAGAACAGGCCAGAAAGUGAAUCCAGGGAACACAGGCAAAUUAUUUGUGGGGGUAGGAAUCUCAAGAAUUGCAAAAGUCAAGUAUGGAGAGUGUGGACAAGGUUUCAGUGUUAAAUCAGAUGUUAUUACACACCAAAGGACACAUACAGGGGAGAAGCUCUACGUCUGCAGGGAGUGUGGGCGGGGCUUUAGCUGGAAGUCACACCUCCUCAUUCACCAGAGGAUACACACAGGGGAGAAGCCCUAUGUCUGCAGGGAGUGUGGGCGGGGCUUUAGCUGGCAGUCAGUCCUCCUCACUCACCAGAGGACACACACAGGGGAGAAGCCCUAUGUCUGCAGGGAGUGUGGGCGGGGCUUUAGCCGGCAGUCAGUCCUCCUCACUCACCAGAGGAGACACACAGGGGAGAAGCCCUAUGUCUGCAGGGAGUGUGGGCGGGGCUUUAGCCGGCAGUCAGUCCUCCUCACUCACCAGAGGAGACACACAGGGGAGAAGCCCUAUGUCUGCAGGGAGUGUGGGCGGGGCUUUAGCUGGCAGUCAGUCCUCCUCACUCACCAGAGGACACACACAGGGGAGAAGCCCUAUGUCUGCAGGGAGUGUGGGCGGGGCUUUAGCUGGCAGUCAGUCCUCCUCACUCACCAGAGGACACACACAGGGGAGAAGCCCUAUGUCUGCAGGGAGUGUGGGCGGGGCUUUAGCAAUAAGUCACACCUCCUCAGACACCAGAGGACACACACAGGGGAGAAGCCCUAUGUCUGCAGGGAGUGUGGGCGGGGCUUUCGCGAUAAGUCACACCUCCUCAGACACCAGAGGACACACACAGGGGAGAAGCCCUAUGUCUGCAGGGAGUGUGGGCGGGGCUUUAGAGAUAAGUCAAACCUCCUCAGUCACCAGAGGACACACACAGGGGAGAAGCCCUAUGUCUGCAGGGAGUGUGGGCGGGGCUUUAGCAAUAAGUCACACCUCCUCAGACACCAGAGGACACACACAGGGGAGAAGCCCUAUGUCUGCAGGGAGUGUGGGCGGGGCUUUCGCAAUAAGUCACACCUCCUCAGACACCAGAGGACACACACAGGGGAGAAGCCCUACGUCUGCAGGGAGUGUGGGCGGGGCUUUAGCGAUAGGUCAAGCCUCUGCUAUCACCAGAGGACACACACAGGGGAGAAGCCCUACGUCUGCAGGGAGGAUGAGUAAGUCAUUAGUAAUAAAACCUCAUCUCAAUAGCCACAAAAAGACAAAUGUGGUCACCACACACUUGCACACCCCAGCUGUGAGGUGGCUUCAGCGGAAGUCUGCUGACCCCUUAUAUUCCCCGAGAGUAUAAAGAGAUCGGAAAUAACUGAUUAAACAAAUCCGCCACUUUCAUGACUAGAGAUGAGGAAGAACAAGGGAUAGUUCUGUAAGUGUUCGGGGGACAUCAGCAUGUGUGGUUCUUUCCCGCACUGAUCCCCUCCAUUUUUUGUUUGUUUUUUUGCCUCCUGUUCUAAUAAAUUUUGUCUCCAUACAAAUCUGAA